AGACCUGCACCGGGCCAGGCAAGAUGGCGGCCAUGGAGACCGAGACGGCGCCGCUGACCCUAGAGUCGCUGCCCACCGAUCCCCUGCUCCUCAUCUUAUCCUUUUUGGACUAUCGGGAUCUAAUCAACUGUUGUUAUGUCAGUCGAAGACUUAGCCAGCUAUCAAGUCAUGAUCCGCUGUGGAGAAGACAUUGCAAAAAAUACUGGCUGAUAUCUGAGGAAGAGAAAACACAGAAGAAUCAGUGUUGGAAAUCUCUCUUCAUAGAUACUUACUCUGAUGUAGGAAGAUACAUUGACCAUUAUGCUGCUAUUAAAAAGGCCUGGGAUGAUCUCAAGAAAUAUUUGGAGCCCAGGUGUCCUCGGAUGGUUUUAUCUCUGAAAGAGGGUGCUCGAGAGGAAGACCUCGAUGCUGUGGAAGCGCAGAUUGGCUGCAAGCUUCCUGACGAUUAUCGAUGUUCAUACCGAAUUCACAAUGGACAGAAGUUAGUGGUUCCUGGGUUAUUGGGAAGCAUGGCACUGUCUAAUCACUAUCGUUCUGAAGAUUUGUUAGACGUCGAUACAGCUGCCGGAGGAUUCCAGCAGAGACAGGGACUGAAAUACUGUCUCCCUUUAACUUUUUGCAUACAUACUGGUUUGAGUCAGUACAUAGCAGUGGAAGCUGCAGAGGGCCGAAACAAAAAUGAAGUUUUCUACCAAUGUCCAGACCAAAUGGCUCGAAAUCCAGCUGCUAUUGACAUGUUUAUUAUAGGUGCUACUUUUACUGACUGGUUUACCUCUUAUGUCAAAAAUGUUGUAUCAGGUGGCUUCCCCAUCAUCAGAGACCAAAUUUUCAGAUAUGUUCACGAUCCAGAAUGUGUAGCAACAACUGGGGAUAUUACUGUGUCAGUUUCCACAUCGUUUCUGCCAGAACUUAGCUCUGUACAUCCACCCCACUAUUUCUUCACAUACCGAAUCAGGAUUGAAAUGUCAAAAGAUGCACUUCCUGAGAAGGCCUGUCAGUUGGACAGUCGCUAUUGGAGAAUAACAAAUGCUAAGGGUGACGUGGAAGAAGUUCAAGGACCUGGAGUAGUUGGUGAAUUUCCAAUCAUCAGCCCAGGUCGGGUAUAUGAAUACACAAGCUGUACCACAUUCUCUACAACAUCAGGAUACAUGGAAGGAUAUUAUACCUUCCAUUUUCUUUACUUUAAAGACAAGAUCUUUAAUGUUGCCAUUCCCCGAUUCCAUAUGGCAUGUCCAACAUUCAGGGUGUCUAUAGCCCGAUUGGUAAGUUAAAUUUUCCUCUAGUGCUGAUUUACAUGACUUUGUAGGGUUAACACUGCAGAUAAGCCAGGCAAAUAGUUAGUUUAUAAAUAGUGUUCCAGAGAACCCUAGAGAUUUUGAGAAAGUAUCUUGGGGGUCAUGUGAAUUUGUUGAGAGAAAUGGACAAGUAAAUGAGGCUCCAUAGUCUCUAACCAGAGAAUUUCUGCUGUUUUAAAGAUUCAACUUGUUUUUCACUGUUCAGUGGCCUAAAUGUAGAUUAUGAGAAAUACCACAUUAGACCAGUAGAAUCAGCUUUAAGACUGGGAAAACAACUUCUUACAGUGUUUUUGCUCAAACUUCCAAUUUAAUGUCAAAUAAACAAAUAUUCCAUAAAGAUCAUUAUAAAGAAAAUUUAAUGUGUGGAUGUGUACUUUUGGCAGUCUCUCUGGGAUCAUUUCUUAAGUCAACUAGGUAUAUUUUUUAAAAUCUCGUUUUUAGGGUUACCUUAUGACAAGUGUAACAGUAACUCCAACCUUAGAGACUAUAACAUGAUUAAAGAAAGUUAUGAAGCUCCAGUUAUACAAUGGGGAUAAAAUAUGAAUUAUAUACCCAGAAUGCAAUUGAGUUGUAGGUGUUGAAUCUUUGGAAAAUGCCCUCUAGCUUCUGGAAUGACCCUGAUGGAUGGGUUUAAGUUUGGAAAGAUGGACAUGAUAUUAAUCUGAUCCAGAGCUGACACAUUUUCAACUCCAGUUUGAAAAGAGAAGGAUGAUAAUGAGACUUUGGGCCAUUACCUGUGUGGCAUAUCUAGUGAAAAGAAUCUACAGUGUGCGUUUGGAAGUGAAGAUUUAGAUUUCUUCCCAGUGGAGGAAUGCCAGAAACUGUAUUUCCAGUACUGGGAAUUUGCUGCUUUGCAUAACAGAAUUCCUUUUUUGACUGGCCCAGUAUCUGUAUGAGUUUGGAAUAAUCUUUUCCCUAAAUGUUUGAUAUGAUUCAUCACUGAAGUUAUCUGGGGCUAGAGUUCUGUUUGUGGGAAAAUUUUGAAAUUUGAAUUUAAUUUCUUUAAUAUUCAUAUUUUCUAUUUCUUCUUGUUUCAGUUUUGGUAAUUUGUGCCUUUCAAGGAAUUUGUCCAUUCCAUCUAAAUGUUGAAUUUAUUGGUAUAAAGUUAUUGACAGUAUUCCCUUGAUAUCCUUUUAAUGGCUACAAAAGCCAUAGUCACUUGUCCUCUUUUGUUCUUAAUAUUGUUAAUUUAUAUCUUCUCUUUUGUUCAUUGCUUUAGUUAGGGGUUUGUAAUUUUUAUUGAUCAUUUAAAGGAGCAACUUUUGGUUUUACUAAUUUUCUCUAUUUGCUUAUUUUCUAUCGCAUUGAUUUCUGCAGUUAUCUUUAUUUCUUUCCUUCUACUUUGAGUUUGCUUUUCUUCUAGCUUUUUUAAGGUAGAAGUUUAUAUUAGUAAUUUUAGAACUUUUCUCUCUCCAAGCACUGUUUUAGCUGCAUUUCACAAGUUUUGAUGUGUUUUCAUGAACGCGUAGUUCAAAAUAGUGUCAGAUUUCCCUUGUAAUUUAAUUUUGAUCUAUGACUUUUCUAGAAAUGUGUUAAUUUUCAAACAUUUGGGGGAGUUUUCAGUUAUCUUUUGGCUAUCGAUUUUUUAAAUUUAUUGUGGUUAGAGAAUUUGCUCUGUAUUUUCAAUCCUAAAUGUUUUAUGGCCCAAAAUUAUGGUUUAUCUUGGUAAAUGAUCCUUGUAUAUUUGAAAAUAAUGUACAUUCUGCUAUUUUGGGGAAUAUUACUCUAUAAAUGAUAGGUCAAAUCGGUUGACAGUUUUUUUCAAGUCUUCUGUAUACUUGCUGAUUUUUUUUUUUUUUGGUCUUUGUCCUAUCAACAAGUGAGAGAUGAUUGUUGAAAUCUCCAAAUAUAAUUAUAGUUUUUUGUUUCUCUUUUUAGUUCUGUCAGGUUUGCUUCAUGUAUUUUGAAGCUGUAUAAUUAUAUGCAAAUAUGCUAAGGAUUAUUAUGUAUUUUUAAUGACAUAAUUCUUUCAUCAUUAUGAAAUCUCCAUCUUUAUCGCUGAUAAUAUUCCUUGUCCUAAAGUUCAAAGAGCAUUGAGGUGUGUUUUGGCAGGCAGUUGAGUUACUAUUGGGUCGACUUGAUCCUUUGGAAUCUUGUUUGUUUUUAAUGUUUGUUAGGGUGGGUGUAAAGUUGUCUUUAUUUAAGGACGGUGGUUGUCAACUUUCAGUCUCAUGACCCCCUGAAACUCUAAAAACUUAUUGAGGACUCCGAAGAAUUCUUGCUUAUGUGGAUUGUAUUAAUGCUUACCAUAUCAGAAAUUAAAACUGAGAAAUAAGUAAAACAAUAUUUACUUAUUAGUUCCUUUUCAAAUGACAAUAAUAAACCCAUUUCAUGUUCAGCUCUCUCUUAACUAUGUUCUUUCUUAUUAGUUUUCGUUUCCUUCUAACCACAAAUAAACAUAUAAAAUCUUGACCUGCCUUGUGGAAAAUGUUUUCUCUCAAGGAUGAGAAAUAAAAUGAGAAUUCUGGACUUACUUCUUAUCAACAUUAAAAAAGCCAUGGGGGUUGUAUUUGUUGACCUUUCCUGUUUGUAUAUUAGUUUUCUGAUAUGGAGAAUUGUUCUGCUUUUUCGUCCUCUACCAGUCUGAUUAAUUCGUAGGCUUAACACUUCCUUUUUCUUUCUCCUUGGAAUGCCUCUUGGGAUAUGCAUUAGUUGGUCUUAUGUCUUUUCUUGGUCUAGGUGGUGUGUGUGUUUGGCUUGUUUGGGGCACUUUUAGAGGCUCCAGCUGCACAUUUCCACUCCUCUCUGUGUGUUCCUCUCUGCAUCUGCUGUUUGUGUGUGUACACUUUUUUUCUGAGCAAUCUUUCUCCUUAGCCACAUUGAGUUCUUUAACAGUUUUUCUGUUUUCUUCUUCAUUAAGAUAAUUAAUAAUCAUACUACUCACAUAUCAUGUUUUAGAACUUCCUAAGCCUUUCCCUUUCCCACCUUUUGGACCUCCUAACUGAAUUUCAAAGUCUUCAUUCCUUAGAUUAAAAAAAUAAAUCCAAAGAUAAAAGAAUGUAAUGUCUUAUAAGUCGUAUCAGUGUAUAUUUUCUCUGUUAUUGUUGUUAGUGUUAUAAUAAAUCCUAAGUGACACAAUUCCUUUCUCCUACAUUAAUUCAUUUGCUUGUACAACAACUAUUUAUUGAGCACUGUGAUUAACAAUAUAAUCAAAUUCCCUGCCUUGGAAUUUACAUUCCAAUUCAAAGAGACAAACUGUAACAAUAAACACUAUGUCCUUAUAUUAAGUAGUAAUAAGUGCUGUGGAGAAACAGCAGAGUAAAGGGGAUAAAGAACGUAUUGUUAGGUUGUUCUAAUAUAAAGAUGUGUCAGGAGAGGCCUUGGUGACAUUUAAGCUGAAACGUGAAAGGAGCAGAGGGAAUUAGGUGGAUAUGUGGGAGACGAGAGGUCGAAGCAAAGGAGCAGCACGUGUGGAGGUUCCGAAACAGUAAUGUGCUUGGUGUGCUUGACCCAAGGAGGCCAGUGUAGCUGGAGUGCAGUGAACAACAGGGAGAGGGGCUGGAGAUUAGAUCAGAGUGUUAAUGGGGUGGUGGAUCACGUAACACCAUAAAAGCCUUGGUGGAAGGACUCUGGCUGACAUCACGCCCCAAGUUGCCCCAUACUUUCCAGAAUACCAAGUAGGUCCUUGCUGUUCAGAAUUCUGUUCAAUGUAGCAGCCCCUCCCAUUGCGUCUUCAAAUGUGUGAGAGAGAACAUUGACAGCAGAGUAAGUCAUGGCUUGAUUACAGACAUUGCAUGGGCAGAAUUGACAUUUCCAAGAGAUAUUCAGAUGCAUGUUCAACAUCACUACUGUCCUAAUCUGAGAGCCUCCAACAAGGUAAUUUUAAAAUAGAGGCUGUCAUUUCCUUCCAGUGUGGGUUGAUCUUAGAUAUAUACUUAUAACGAAUCGGCAAAGUGACACUGUGAUUUCUGAGUUAGAAAAAGGUAAUAUUCCUUCAGCCUAGGGUUCUGUCUUUCUCUCCUGGGACAUGUGUCUUUGACACCCUGAGCCACCAUGUAAGAAGUCCAGCUACCAUGAAGCCGUCAUGCAGAAGAGACCAUGUAGAGACAUCACACAGAGAUAGAGGGAGGCACCCAGGAGCCCCAGCUGUUUCAGACUCCAGAUAUUUGGAUCAUCCUGCGCGGGUACCAGACAUGUGAAUGAAGAAGCUCGUGAGAUGACUGCAGUUCCAGCUACCAUCGGACUGCAACAUCACGGGACACCCCAACCCAGAACCACCCCACUGAAUACUUCCCAAACACCAACCCACAUGAACCAUGAGAGAUAAUAAUGACUGUUGCUGUUUCAAGCCACUAAAAAAAUAAAAAUAUUUUUUUAAAAAGUAGAGGCUACUGAUGGUUGAAUUGAAAUGAUGUGUCUUUAUGGUAGGAGCUCAAUAAAAAUCUUAGAUCUCUUGUUGACAGUGCAUAAAAGUUACCAGUAGAGGUCAUACUUGAUUAAUAUUUUCAUAUCCUCUUUUCUGUAAGUAUAUAGCUUAAUAAUUAUUAUUCAGUAUAUGAAUAUAAGCUCAGUAAAACUGUAUCUUGGAUUGUUACAAGUGGUCUGUUUGCUACCUUCUGUGAAUUACCAACUACUGUGUAAAAAAUAAGUACUGGCUUAGUGAAAUAUUUACCAUUAAAACCAUACUGAGCUGGGCUGGGUCGCAUGCACCUGUAGUCCCAGCUACUCGGGAGGAUGAGGUGGGAGAACUGCUUGAGCCCAGGAGUUUGAGGCUAGCCUAGGCAACACAGCAAGAACUCGUCUCUAAGAAAAAAUAAUAAUUUUUUUAAAAAGAAGAUCUUCCAUUAAACAACAACAAAAAAAUCACACUGAGCAUUAUUUAACACAAGAUAUAGAAUCCACUCCAGAAUCUUGCAUCAGCAUGUGUGUUGUGAGAAUCCACUGUUCAAGUCUAUGGAAAUUCAUAUUUGGCGUGUCUGGUUGUUUGAAUUCUAGAUAAAUGAGAAUUUACAUGAAAUAACUAAAAAACUGAUAGAUGCUCUUCUUAUCAAAAGAUUGUUUUCUCUUUCAAGGAAAUGGGUCCUGAUGAAUAUGAAGAGAUGGAAGAAGAGGAGGAGGAGGAAGAGGAGGAAGACGAGGAUGAUGAUUCAGCAGAUAUGGAUGAAUCAGAUGAAGAUGAUGAAGAGGAGAGACGGAGGAGAGUCUUUGAUGUUCCCAUUCGCAGACGCCGCUGCUCACGCCUUUUUUAGCAAGCCUUCUGCUGAUGGAAGCACUAGGAUGAUUCUAGGCUGUUAAAUAGAUUUCUCAAUAAUGUAAAUAACUAAAUUGUUCUCUGCAUAUAGCAGGAAAACUAGCAUGAAAUAUUGUUUCAGGCCCUGGGUUCUAUGUGACACUACAUUAGGAAUUGGAUUGUUUGGGUUUGCUUUGUGUUUUUGAGGUAGAGGAAGAAAUGGGAAUCUUUUUUUUCUCUUCCAGGAGUCAGUGGAAGAAUAGUUCUCUAGCUAAGGAAUGGACAUACCUUUGUUUUAAAAUAUUUUAUACUUACAAAAAUCUAGAAAUGGAGAGGGAACUGUUUUGAAUAAGGAUUUAAAAUACCUGCACAAGGAUAGAGAGAAACUAUGUGACUCAUUCUGUGAAAAGACUUCUUGCAGUUGUGAGUUAUUUAGAAAUGAUCAAAAUUUGUAAUUAGGCUAAUCCAUUUAGUGAUUCCUAAUAUUUUGUACUCACAGAGAACUAAUUGACUAAACAACUUGAACGCUAGUGGUUUGUCCUUAGACAAUCUGUCUUUGAAUUUAAAGUCUUUAUCGCUAAGACCUUGACUUUAAAUUUUUCAUCACUACAACCUUGAAUUUAAUUUCAGGUCUUCAACAUGAUGACCUUGGAUUUAAUUUAAAGUCUUCAACACUAUGCGCUUUAUCAUAUUAUUCACAGAUGCAUUUUUGAAAUGUAGUAUGUAAAAGUAUGUAACGUGCUGUUUAUUAACAAAAGAUUGUUCACAACAUCUCAUGUAGUUUAAAUUUGUAAAUACUGCUUCUGUUUUGUUUCUCCUUUAUACACUUGACUGUCUUUGUGAUAAGUGACAUGAAUUUUAUGUUAGGAUUAAGUAUGUUUUCCUGAAACUUGGAUUUUUUUUGUAAUUAUAUAAUUGAGAGUUAAGAAUGAAAUCCUUCAAGUGUUAAAAACUCACAUUUUAAAAGCAAAUUUUGGUUCCAA